AAACUGCCGCGCCGCCCUGCUCCGGGUUUGUCUUCCUCCCUCCGUUUCUCCUUCCGCUGUAUCUAGCAUUUCGGUUCCUGGAAAGGUUACCGGAGCUGCGAUUGGGGCUGGGACCAAAGUUGAGUCCUGGAAAGGGAGCCUGGAGAGCGGCGGUGCUGGGAGGCCCGGCCAGCUCGAUCGCAGGCUUCCACCUGGCGGCCAAUGCUUGUUUGCUACUGAUGGGUGUGAGCAAGUUAGAUAUUCUAUACCGGAGACUUCUCCUAACAAAACUUUUUAUCAGAGGAUGGGGAAGGCCAGAAGAUCUCAAAAGACUCUUUGAAUUCAGAAAGAUGAUUGGAAAUCGGGAAAGAUGCCAGAAUCUGGUUUCAAGCGAUUAUCCAGUACACAUUGAUAAGAUUGAAGAGCAAUCAGAUUGUAAGAUCUUAGAUGGACACUUUGUUUCCCCCAUGGCUCACUAUGUGCCUGAUAUCAUGCCAAUUGAAUCUGUUAUUGCAAGGUUCCAAUUUAUUGUGCCUAAAGAAUGGAACAGCAAAUAUAGACCUGUAUGCAUUCAUCUUGCUGGAACAGGAGAUCAUCAUUACUGGAGGCGACGAACACUAAUGGCCCGUCCUAUGAUUAAAGAAGCCCGAAUGGCUUCUUUAUUGUUAGAAAACCCUUAUUGAUGACGUCAGACUAUUCACAGAAGAAGAAAUGAAACUGGUGCACAGAUAUAAAGAAAUGUUCAACGUUGCUGGAAACCCAAGGACCAAGUGUAAGUAUAUAUCACUUUCAUUUUUGCAGUCUUUUUACCCAAUAUCCAGCAGUAUUAAAAUUUUGGUUGCCUUCAGUUAACCAUUUCUAAAUUGAAUACCUAAAUAUUAUGGGGGGGGGGAGUUCUGUUAUGAAACUGUAGUAUGAAUACUGACUUUAAUUUUUAUUUUUAAGAUUUUUGCAUUUUAAUGUCUGUUAAGGAAAUACAAUAAAAAAUUUUAACAGGUAGACUUAAUAUAUAGUUUAGUUGUGAAACUGUAAAUGAAGAAAUGAUAAAACCCUUUCUUUUUUUUUUUUUGAGACGCAGUCAUUCUGUCACCCAGUCUGGAGUGCACUGGUGCGAUCUCAGCUCACUGGAACCUCUGCCUCCUGGGUUCAAGCGAUUCUCUGCCUCAGCCUCCCAAGUAGCUGGAAUUACAGGCAUGCACCACCACACCUGGCUAAUUUUUGUAUGUUUAGUAGAGAUGGGCUUUCACCAUGUUGGUCAGGCUGGUCUCAAACUCCUGACCUCAAGUGAUCCACCCACCUUGGCCUCCCAAAGUGCUGGGAUUAUAGGCAUGAGCCACUGUGCCCAGCCUACCUUUUCCUUUUUAAGAAGGUCCAGCUUAAAAAAUGUGUCCGACCUUUUUGUGAUGGGAGGAGCUCUUGUUUUAGAAUCUGCAGCUCUCUUGCACUGGCUAGAGAGGGAAGGUUACGGCCCUUUAGGAAUGACUGGAAUAUCCAUGGGAGGACACAUGGCUUCCUUAGCGGUAUCCAACUGGCCUAAGCCCAUGCCAUUGAUUCCAUGCCUGUCUUGGUCCACAGCAUCUGGGGUCUUCACUACGGGUGUGUUGAGUAAAUCAAUUAAUUGGAGGGAGCUGGAAAAGCAAUAUUAUACCCAGACAGUUUAUGAAGAAGAAAUUAUUCACAUGCUUGAAUACUGUGGAACAGAUUCUUUCAAAAUGGGACAAGAGUUUGUGAAACACUUCACUAGCAGUGCAGACAAGCUAACUAACCUUAAUCUGGUUUCCAGAACUUUAAAUUUAGAUAUAUCAAACCAAGUUGUAUCCCAAAAACCUGCUGACUGCCAUAAUUCUAGCAAAACAUCUGUCAGUGCGACAUCAGAAGGACUCUUAUUGCAAGAUACCUCUAAGAUGAAGCGCUUCAAUCAAACACUUUCAACCAACAAAAGUGGUUAUACAAGUCGCAACCCUCAGUCAUACCACCUACUUAGUAAAGAACAAAGCAGAAACAGUCUUCGGAAAGAGUCUUUAAUAUUUAUGAAAGGAGUCAUGGAUGAAUGUACUCAUGUAGCAAAUUUCUCAGUCCCAGUUGAUCCAAGCCUCAUUAUAGUGGUUCAAGCCAAAGAAGAUGCCUAUAUUCCACGAACAGGAGUUCGAAGUUUACAAGAAAUUUGGCCUGGUUGUGAAAUCCGAUACUUAGAAGGGGGUCAUAUUAGUGCUUAUCUUUUUAAACAAGGACUCUUCAGACAAGCCAUCUAUGAUGCAUUUGACCGCUUCCUCCAUAAAUACGCUAACUAGUUGGAUUAUUAUAUGUAACCAGUGUGGCCAUGAUGUUUCUUACAAAAGGGAGCUUCAUCCUGUGAUCAUGUGAAGGACAAGCAGACAGCACUAAUAUAUCUAAUCGCUAUCAAUUUGGUCUGGAAUUCAUUGUUACACAUCAGUUAACUAUAAACUUCGAAUACAUUUGAAUAAUUUCAAGAUAAUAUUUGAAGUAAAUAAUGUUAAAGUGUUUUUACUAUUGUUUAUUGGAAUCCCAUAUAUUCAGUGUUUAGUCUGUUGUUACUGUUUAUGAAAAACUAAAUUUUUAAUCAUGAAUAAUUUAUUAAAUUAAAUAAAUUUAUUCAUAGAAACUUUUCUGGGUUUUAGUAAAAUUGCUAAAUCAAACCAAGAUUUUAAUAUAUCAGCAUUUACUUUGUACCCUUAUAACAUUUCACUCUUGACUUGAUUUGAGAAACAUGUUUAUUUUUUGAAUGUUCUUGUGUUCAACUAAUUUUCUGCUGUGGAAAUAAAUACUUAUGAUAUAUAAAAUCAGUGUUAACUUUGAAUUCUAAAAUAUCCUGAUAGCUUCAUAGAUAAGUGCUUUUCUUUUUCUUUUUUUUUUCUUUUAACAUGUACCUCUACUUGAAUGUAAGUGCUUUUAAUAAUCAAAGUGAGUGGCAGGGUGCGGUGGCUCACGCCUGUAAUCCCAGCACUGGGAUGCUGAAGCGGGCAGAUUACCUGAGGUUGGGAGUUCAAGACCAGCCUGACCAAUAUAGAGAAACCCCCUCUCUACUACAAAUACAAAAAAUUAGCCAAGCAUGGUGGCGCAUGCCUAUAAUCCCAGAUACUCAGGAGGCAGAGGCAGGAGAAUCGCUUGAACCCGGGAGGCAGAGGUUGCGGUGAUCCGAGAUCACACCAUUGCACUCCAGCCUGGGCAACAAGAGUGAAACUCCGUCUCAAAAUAAUAAUAAUAACCAAAAUGAGUGUUCUGCAGAUAAAAUGCAUUAGACUUUGCUAGACUAAAACUUUACUAAAGAUUAGGGUUUUUAAAAAAUGCCAAUAGGCCGGGUGCAGUGGCUCAUGCCUGUAAUCCCAGCACUUUGGGACGCUCAGGCGGGCGGAUCACAAGGUCAGGAGUUUAAGACCAGCCUGGCCAACAUGGUGAAACCCCAUGUCUACUAAAAGUACAAAAAAAUUAGCCGGGCAUUGUGGCGUGUGCCUGUAAUCCCAGCUACUCAGGAGGCUGAGGCAGGAGAAUUGGUUGAACCAAGGAGGCGGAGGUUGCACUGAGCUGAGAUUGCGCCACUGCACUCCAGCCUGGGCAACAGAGCAAAACUCCAUCUCAAAAAAAAAAAAAAAAAAAAAAAAAAAUUAAGCCGGGCAUGGUGGCAGGCACCUGUAAUCCCAGCUACUCGGGAGGCUGAGGCAGGAGAAUUGCUUGAACCCGGGAGGCAGAAGUUGCAGUGAGCGGAGAUCGCACCACUGCACUCCAGCCUAGGAGAAGGAGCAAGACUCUGUCUCAAAACAAAACAAAAUGCCAAACUUAUUUCUCCCUACUAAAAAGUUUCAAUUCACAAAAAUGGAAACAUUGGAAGACCUGUUGCAUUAACUGACGGAGUGCAGUGGCAUGAUCUUGGCUCACUGCGACCUCCGCCUCUCAGGUUCAAGCGGUUCUCCUGCCUCCACCUGAGUAGCUGAGAUUACAGGUGCCCGCCACCAUGCCUGGCUAAUUUUUGUAUUUUUAAUAGACACGAGGUUUCACCAUGUUGGCCAAGCUGGUCUCGAAUUCCUGACCUCAAGUGAUAUGCCUGCCUUGGCCUCCCAAAGUGCUGGGAUUAUAGGUUUGAGCCACCACACCCGACCUGACAUUUUAUUUUUAUUUUUUUAAUUACAUUUUUCUAUAUGCUUAUUCUUUGGAUUGCUAACCAUCUAACUACCCAAAUACUUAACAGCCUUGGCUUUUAAUUUCAAAAUUUAAUAGACACAUAUGCAAUUGAUUUGUCCCAUAUAAACUUUAUUUUACAGAAAAUAUUUAAAGUUUUAUGUAAUAGCUAUUAACUCUCUUAAAUGGGGUUUAUAUGGCUCGAUUUGGUGCUUUCUUUUUAUGUUAAACUUCUCUAGCUGUCAGCUAAAAUGUUAAAAAAGUCGAAAAUAUUUUAGGGUAUUGUGUGAAGUUUUACAGUAGGUAUUUUUGAGUUUUGUUUGAAAUCUGUGUUGUCUGUGAAUUAUUUUUAAAUAGGGAUUCUUAGUCUACUAACGAUAUUUGAAUUAUAAUGUGCCUUUGCAGUCUUUUUAAAGGAGAUUUCAUUUGUCACCUCUAUGCCUCUAUCAUCUUAAUUUUUUACAAAUAUUUAAAAAUUAUUAAUGUGAAGUUAUUGAUGGUAGACAAAGUAGUAACUUCUUUCAAACUACUUUGGCAUAACAAGCCAACACUGUACAGCUCUUUGAGCUAUAAGCAAUUUUACAUGUUCAGAUGAGAACCUUUAGUUUUAACCAAAAGUAUAACAUCUACUAAAGUUCUUCCACAAAAUACUUUUUAAAAUAAAACUUGUCAACUGAAUUACGAUUUUCUUAUAUUAUGUAUAUAGUGAGGUUAUAUGAUUGAAUGCUUUUUGAACAAUGGUUUUAGUAAAACAAAUACUUUAUUAUUGUUCACAUAAACAUUUCUUACUAAGCAAUAAUGUACUAUGUUGUGUGAAUUUCUAUUGUUAAAAAAAUGAAAUGUUGAUUUAGUUUUAAUUCUUAGGCAUAACUAACUUUUCUCAAAUAAAGUGUGAAAGAAAGUAUUUUUAAAAUUUCAUCUCUUAACCAGAUGUUUUAAGAAUAUAUCCCUAGGCCGGGUGCAGUGGCUCACACCUGUAAUCCCAGCACUUUGGGAGGCCGAGGUGGGGGGACCACCUGAGGUUGGGAGUUCGAGACUAGCCUGACCAAUAUGGAGAAACCCCAUCUCUAUUAAAAAUACAAAAUUUUUAAAAAAAAUACAAAAUUAGCCAGGCGUGGUGGCACAUGCCUGUAAUCCCAGCUACUCAGGAGGCUGAGCCAGGAGAAUCGCUUGAACCCGGGAGACGGAGGUUGCAGUAAGCCGAGAUUGUGCCAUUGCACUCCAGCCUGGGCAACAAGAGCAAAACUCUGUCUCAAAAAAUAUAUAUAUAUCCCUAAAACUACCUCAGUUGAAGAAUUCAAAGUGCAAAAUAACUUUUCUUAGGAUUUUUUAAUCUAUUCCCCCCAAAAUGGUGGCUUAAGUGUUCUCAAAUACAUAAAUAUACACAUAUACGUAUAUGUAUACGUUUUAUAUAUAUAUACACACACACGUAUGUGUGUAUAUAUAUGUAUGUACGUAUAUAUAUGUAUUAUAUAUACACACAUAUGCAUAUAUAUAUAUAUAUAUAUAUAUAUAUAUAUAUAUAUAUAAUCUCAAAGAAGUGCGGUCUGCCAUUUAUCUGCCAUUUUGAGGAUUUAGGUACUACAUAAAAUAUUAGAAAUUCAUUUAGACCAGAUCUGUAAACUGGUAGUUCACAUAGGCCAGUUUGACCCACAGUUAUUUUAUUAGAUGUACAUAAUGUUUCAAAAAUGUUUGAAUUUGAAAAGUCUUUUGAUUGGGUGUGUGUUCCCCAGUUUGCCACAGCCUACUGGACUUCCCUCUUAUAUCAGACAACUUCUCUACUUUGUAGUUCCUGCUCAGCCCUGAAGACCUCUAAGUUUGAGACCCCUGAUUUAGAUCUGUAAUUAGAAAAAGGUUCUGAAUUUCAUGAUUUGCUAAUGUAAUUACUAUUAAGUCAUUUUAGCAUGUGCAUUUUAGAGUCCUUCUUUGUAUUUUUGUAAUGUGGUGCUUUCUCUCAUAAAGAUAAUUGAAUUGUUAACACUGUAAUUGAAAUUUUAAAAAUCAUUUCCAAAUCUUUUAUUAUAUUUCACAGUAAAAGUCUAUUUAAAAAGCUAAUCAUUUGUGCUUUUUUUCAAGAGGUAUUAUUGUAAAUACGGUAGACACAUGUCACAUUUGAUUAAUGUACCCAAACUUGAACUGAGUGUAUAUGUUCCCUCUUUGUUAUUAUGCCCUAAACAAGGUAAGACAGAAAUAAGCAAGGGAGGCUCUAGCAGAACAGUAUCAGUAUCUCUAUAAAAAUAACCAAAAUUUUCCCCAAAUAUGUGUGAUCUGAGGGAAAUAAACAUUCUUACAGACCA